AGAGCAUGGCGGCGGGCGAGCUUGAGGGUGGCAAACCCCUGAGCGGGCUGCUGAAUGCGCUGGCCCAGGACACUUUCCACGGGUACCCCGGCAUCACAGAGGAGCUGCUACGGAGCCAGCUAUAUCCAGAGGUGCCACCCGAGGAGUUCCGCCCCUUUCUGGCAAAGAUGAGGGGGAUUCUUAAGUCUAUUGCGUCUGCAGACAUGGAUUUCAACCAGCUGGAGGCAUUCUUGACUGCUCAAACCAAAAAGCAAGGUGGGAUCACAUCUGACCAAGCUGCUGUCAUUUCCAAAUUCUGGAAGAGCCACAAGACAAAAAUCCGUGAGAGCCUCAUGAACCAGAGCCGCUGGAAUAGCGGGCUUCGGGGCCUGAGCUGGAGAGUUGAUGGCAAGUCUCAGUCAAGGCACUCAGCUCAAAUACACACACCUGUUGCCAUUAUAGAGCUGGAAUUAGGCAAAUAUGGACAGCCCGCUGUCAGUAAGAAGUAGCAAGAAGUAAAUUGGCAGAAAAGCUAUUAUAAGCAAAAGGAAGAUUCACUUAGCUAGUGAUUCAAAGCAUCACUAUAUGUCAGACUCAUCUGAGGAGCUUAAAAAGAAAUUAAGAUGCCCAGACCCCAUCUCAAAGUAAGUGGCUUUACUUUAAUUUGAGUGAAGGAAGAUUUCUUCUCUGAGGUGAGCUGAGCUUUGAAUGACAAGAAGGAGGCAGCCCCAGGAAGAUCUGGGGGCACAAAAUACAGGCAGAGGGAGCAACCAAGGCAAGAAAUUAGCCUUGUUAAGAAUUUUAAGUGUAAUGGGAAGCCAUUAGAGGGUUUUAAACAAGGAAAGAUGUGAUGUGACUUAUAUUCUAAUAGGAUUGCCUUGAUUCACCUAUGGAGAAUGGAUUUCUGGGAUCUCAGUACUGGGAUACUGAGAUCCCAGGGGGAAAAUAUCACUAAGGUUGGAAUUGCUUUUCUGCACAUUAAAAGCAAUUCUCUUUUUCCUUGAAACCUCCAUGUGAUGUUAAUUAGGUAAAUGGGAUUUCAAGGAAAAAAAAAAUACAAAACAACAAAAAGAAAAACUGUUAUCCUUCAUUCUCUUAAUAAGAUGAGGUAUUCAGAAAUGAAUGGAGCCAAUAUUAAUAUUCCACUCCAAAAAAUAGUAGAAAUGAGUUUACAUGGACUUCUCACAAUCUCCAUUCCACAUUUCCAUCUCUGUUUCUCAUUUAUGACAGGUCCCUUCCUUUAAAAACUUUUUUUAUUAUAAUAUGUUCCAAAACUUGUUUGUCAAACCUAGGGAUAACUAAUAAAAAUCAGUAUUGUAGGGGGAAAAAAGUGAAAGCAGGAGGCCACUUACUGGGCUCUCACAGUGGUCCAGGUGAGAUAACGGCAUGGAAAUAGAGGUAAUUUUAAGGAAGUGAAGUGAGCAGGUAGAGUGUAGGUUUUGAAUAUGGGUGAGUUGCUUUGAGUUGACUUGGAAGGGAUGUAGAGAAUGAGAGAAAGUGAGGAAUUGGGGGUAACACCUUGUUUUUUCUUGUAAGACUAUGUUAGCAUAAUUUGGUAAUUCUAGUCAUUGUUAAAACAGUCUUAUUGCAGUGUUGACUGUCUAACAUACAACUUGAGUUUUCUGGUAGCUAUAAUUACCCCUUCCACUUGGGGAAAAAUAUGAAAGAAAUCAUUUAACAUUUGGCAGUUAAGAAGAUGUUGUUUGUGCUGAAGUAAUUUUAUUUUUAAAACUCUCAACUUACAGAGAGAUGCACUUGAGAUUACUGAACAUAAAUUUUUUAUAGACUUUAAAAGAAAAUCAUUGUUUCUUAUGAUGUGCCCUUUCUUAUGUAUACUAUACCCAAUAAAAUGAUUUAAAGAGGAGGAGAGAAAAAGAUGAGUGUCUUUGCAGAUUCAUUGACCCUGUGAGAAUAGGGCUUUGGCACUGCUGAAGUCCUCAGCCUCUGACUAGUAGCUUGCCAGCACGCAGCCCCUGGUGUUGGACUUCGUUCAGCUGUUCAGGCUGUCUGUUUCUAUUCUUGCAGACAGAUGGGGUGCUUGAGAGGAAGCCAGGAAGCCAAGCCUUAAGAGGACUUGGAAGCAAUUUUUGGAUAUAAAUCCCUUGUCCUAAACUCAGGGCAACAGUGUAUCCUGCCCAGCAGUGUUGAACUGCCUGUGUUUGUCUAGUAUGUGUGUACUGGCUGGUUGGCUCUGGGCUUCAUUCCAUGUAUGCCACUGCUCUAUUGCCAAGAUAAAUGUAGAAGGCCUCUGGCCCAAGCCCUUCUUUAGUACUUAAAAAAAAAAAAUUGUGGUAAAAUACACAUAACAAAAUUUUACCAUUUUAACCUUUUUUUUUUUUUUUUUUUUUUUUUUUUUUUUUUUUUGAGACAGAGUCUUGCUCUGUCACCCAGGCUGGAAUGCAGUGGUGCAAUCUUGGCUCACUGCAACCUCUACCUCCUGGGUUCAGGCGAUUCUUCUGUCUCAGCCUCCCGAGUAGCUGGGACUACAGGUGUGCACCACCACGCCAGGCUAAUUUUUGUAUUUUUAGUAGAGAUGGGGUGUCACCAUAUUGGCUUGGCCAGUAUGGUCUUGAACUCCUGACCUCAUGAUCCACCCCCCUCAGCCUCCCAAAGUGCUGGGAUUACAGGUGUGAGCCACUGCGCCCGGCCAUUUCAGCAGUUUUUAAGUGUACAGUCCAGUGGUAUUAAGUACAGCCCAGUGGUAUUAAGUACAGAUGGUUUUCUUUUUUAAGAGAUGGCAGUCUUGCCACCCAGGCUGGAGUACAGUGGCAUGAUCAUAGCUUACUGUAGCCUCAAGUCCUGGGCUCAAGCAGUCCUCCUGCCUCCACCUCCCAAAGCACUCGGAUUACAGAUGAGCCACUGCAUCCAACCCAUUCAUGAUGUUGUAUAACCAUCACCACUAUUUGCAGAUCUUUCUUUUUUAAAUCCCAAACAGAAAUUCAGUACACAUUAAACAAUAAUUCCCAAUUUCCAUCUCUUCAGCCCCUGGUAACCUCUUUUCUACUUUUUUCUCUGUGUAUUUGCCUAUUCUAGGUACCUCAUAUAAAUAGAACCACACAAUAUUUGUCCUUUUGUGUCUGGUUUAUUUUACACAUAGUGUCUUCAACUUUUAUCGUUGUUGUAGUACAUAUCAGGAUUUCAUUCCUUUUAAAGGCUGAAUAAUAUUCCAUUGUGUACAUAUACCACAUUUUGUUUAUCCAUUUAUCUGUUGAUGGAUAUUUGAGUUGUUUCCACCUUUUGGCUCUUGUGACUAAUCUGCUGUGAACAUGGGUAUACAAAUAUCUAUUUUAGUCUCUGUUUUUAAUUCUUUUGGGUAUAUACUAGGAGUGGACUUGUUGGAUCAUACGGUAAUUCUAUGUUUUAACUUUUUAAGGAACUGACAAACUAUUUUCUACAGCAGUUGCUCAAUUUUACGGUUUUUUGCAGUACAUGAAGUUUCCAGUUUCUGUACAUCCUCACUAACACUUGUUAGUUUCUGGGUUUUUUUUUUUUUUCUUUUUUUUUUUUGAUAGUUGUCAUCCGAAUGUAUAUAAAGUGGUAUCUCAUUUAGUUUUGAGUUGAAGUCCUUAAUGAUUAGAGAUGUUGAACAUCUUUUUAUGUGCUUAUUGGGUUUGCCCUUUUUGUUUGUUUUUUUGAGACAAGAGUCUUGCUCCAUCUCCCAGGCCGGAGUGCAGUGGUGCAAUCUUGGCUCACUGAAACCUCCGCCUCCCAAGUUCAAGUCAUUCUCUUGCUCAGCAUCCUGAGUAGCUGGGAUUACAGGCACACACCACCACACCUGGCUAAUUUUUGUAUUUUUAGUAGAGACAGGGUUUCACCACUUUUGGCCAGGCUGGUCUUGAACGCCUGACCUCAGGCAAUCUACCUGCCUUGGCCUCCCAAAGUGCUGGGAUUACAUGCGUGAGCCACGAUGCCCGGCCAGGUUUGCCCAUUUUCAAAAAUCUUUUUUAUUUUUCUUUCUUUUCUUUUUGUCUCUCUUUUUUCUUUUCUUUUCUUUUUUUUUUUUUUUUUUUCGAGACAGGGUCUUGCUCUAUCGCCCAAGCUGGAGUGCAGUGGCACAAUCUCGGCUCACUGCAACCUCUGCCUCCCAAGCUCCAGUGUUCCUCCCACCUCAGCCACCUGAGUAGCUGGGACUACAGGUGCAAGCUACCAUGCCUGGUUAAUUUUUUAUAUUUUUUGUAGAGACGGGGUUUUGCCAUGUUGCCCAGGCUGGUCUUGAACUCCUGGGCUGAAGCAAGCCACUGCCUCGGCCUUGCAAAGUGCUGGGAUUAUAAGCAUGAGCCACUGAACCCAGCCUCUUUUUUUUUUUUUUUCCUACACCAAACACCUGAACUCAUUUUAUGCACUUUUAUUGUUUUUUUUGUUGUUGAGUUGUAGGAGUUUUUUUAAAUGUAUUCAGGAUAUCAAUCACAUAUUAGAUAUAUGGAUUUGCAAAUAUUUUCUCCCGGUCUGGGUUUUCACUCCCCUCCAGAUCAUAUCCUUUGAUGCAUAAAAGUUUUAAAUUUUGAUGUGGUCCAGUUUAUUUUUACUUUUGUUGCCUGUGCUUUUGGUAUCCUAUCCAAGAAGUCAUUGCCAAAUCCAAUGUCAUGAAACUUUUCCUCUCUGUUUUCUACUAAGGGUUCUAUAGUUUUCACUCUUAGGCUUAGGUCUUUGAUCCACUCGAGUUAAUUUUUUCAUAUGAUAUGAGGCCAUUCUUAACAUUUUGUAUGGAUUUUUAAAAAAUGAUUUAUGCUACUAGGGAAACAGAAAAAAGGACUUCUGAACUUGAAGCUGAUAAGUUGUAAAUUUAUCAUGUUUCUGAAUUUUCUAGAUAACUCUGUAUAAUUAAUUAAACAGAGCUCUUAUCACCCAAGACAUUAAUGAGUGGUAGUCUCUAGGAACCAGCUCAGAUUAACUGCCAAAUAAGCUAAACUUCCUUUUUAUUGCCAGAGUUAUUAACCUAAGUGGAUUAUAAGUCAAUAACAGAGGAAAUAUAUCUGAAUUUUAAUGAGCCAUUUUAUAGUCUUGUGGAUACAGUACAAAAGCCUGAACUGAAUUAUGAUAAACCUAGUGAAUGUAACAGUGUUGAUCACAAAAUUAGUUUGAUCUUUGAUCCUGUGAUACUGGCCUCCGUCCACACACACACUUCUUAGUCUAAAGAAAACAGCCUAGUCUUCUUAGAAUAUCAUUUAAAGGCUGGGUGCAAUGGCUCAUGCCUCUUAUGCUAACACUUUGAGAGGCCAAGGCAGGCAGAUCACUUGAGCCCAGGAGUUCAAGACCAGCCUGGGCAACAUGGUGAAACCCUAUCUCUACAAAAAAUUAAAAAAAAUUAGCAGGGCAUGGUGGUGCACACCUGUAGUCCCAGCUGCUUGGUAGACUGAAGUGGGAGGAUUGCCUGGGCCCAGGAGUUUGAGGCUGCAGUGAGCUGUGAUCAUGCCACUGCACUCCAGCCUGGGUGACAAGAGUGAGACCCUGUCUCCAAAAAAAGAAAAAAAAAAGAAAAAUGAAGGUAUCUUUUGGCUGUGUGGCUCUGUUCAUGUAAUUCUUUAAAAACGCUGACUUCAGGCUGGGCAUGGUGGCUCACGCCUAUAAUACCAGCACUUUGGGAGGCCAAGGCAGAACGAUUGUUUGAGUUGAGAACAGGAGGUCAAGAUCAGCCUGGGCAACACAGGAAGACCCCAUCUCUACAAAAAAUUUUUAAAAUUACCUGAGCAU